AUAGGUAGGUAGUGGUUUAAUUUUUUCAUAAAGGCAAAUGAUGUUGACUCUCUUAUAUGGUUGUUCACCAUCUGUAUAUUUUCUUUGGGGAAAUGUCUUUUUAUAUCUUUUGCCCAUUUUUCUGAUUGGAUUGUUUGUUUUACUGUCUAAUCUGAUACAGGAAAAUAUCUCAUUGGUGUUUGAAUUGGCAUUUCUUUAGUAUUUGGUGAGAAUGAACUUUUUGUCAUGUUUAUUUCUUUUUAAAAGUUACUGAAUUAUUAACUGCAUUAAUUGUUUUUGUCAUUUCAUAAUUGUGGGUUUCUAUUUCUAAAUAGACUUGAAAAAAAGUAUCAGCAAUUUCAUUUGUAUUCAUCACAGUACCUUAAACUAUCAGGCUCUUGAUAAAGAUUUAUUGUUUAGUUGGUUGAAAAUAGUUGUAAUAUUGGGGUGAUAAUCUAGGUUGGCCUUGAUUAAUCUAGGUAGUUGAGUAUUUUAGGUUUAUCCAGUUUUACCAUUUUCUGGCGUGUAUUGACUAAUUGGUUCACUUAACCAAAUGUUCAUUCCUUUUAUUUUUACUUGAUGUUUUAGUGCAAAUCUGAUUCGACACCUAAUAAUAUAGAGCUGUGACAUUAGGGUUGUUUGGCUUAUCAUAUUCCUGCCACUACAGAAAGAUUAAUUUUGACUCAAAGCUUUCUAAGAAAGUGUUUUAAUACUUCUCUAUUCCAAACUCUAAUGGGUUUUUUUUCCCAUUCUGUUUAUUGAUGUAAAUUAUAAAUGAUCCCUGAAAUUCCUCUUGGGCUUGUUUUCUUCUUUAUCUCACCAGAUUCACCAGAGGCUUUACCUCUGCGAAGCCUCAAAUCUCAACUUGCCUCUGAACUGAUAAUACAGAAUAGAAUCUGUAUGUUAUGUGCACUCAAAAUCCAACAUGUAAAAUGACUGCAAAAAUUAUUUUCUUCCAGAAAUCCUUCCCAAACUAGUUUUGGGUGGGAAAAAUAAAGUAUUGGAUUUUAUUUUUGGUUAGCCUUUUUUUUUAAUUUAAAUUAAAAUUUUUUUAGGAAUGGGAGUCUCGCUAUGUUGCUCAGACUGGUCUUGAACGGAACUCCUCGCCUCAAGCCAUCCUCCCACCUCCGCCUCCUGAGUCACUGGGAUUACAGGCAUGAGCCAUUGACCUCAGCUCUGUUUAACCUUUAAAAUGGAGGAAGGAAGAACUCUGGGUCUGGCUGGCCUGACUCCAGAUUAUUUCCACCGACAGCAGAGGGUGCCUGUCCUUGCUUGUGACGGUCCAGCACACAGAACGCUAUGUCACCCUGUUUGCCUCUAUCAUCCUCAAAUGUGACUACACCACCUCUGCCCAGCUCCAGGACGUGGUGGUGACAUGGCGCUUCAAGUCCUUCUGCAAGGACCCUAUCUUUGACUACUACUCAGCGUCAUACCAGGCAGCUUUAUCCCUGGGCCAGGACCCAUCCAAUGACUGCAACGACAACCAGCGGGAAGUUCGCAUAGUGGCCCAGCGGCGGGGGCAGAAUGAGCCCGUGCUGGGGGUAGAUUACCGGCAGCGCAAGAUCACCAUCCAGAACCGAGCAGAUCUCGUGAUAAAUGAAGUGAUGUGGUGGGACCAUGGAGUGUAUUACUGCACCAUUGAGGCUCCAGGGGACACAUCAGGAGACCCCGAUAAGGAAGUAAAGCUCAUCGUCCUACACUGGCUGACAGUGAUCUUCAUCAUCCUGGGAGCCCUCCUCCUCCUGCUGCUGAUUGGAGUGUGCUGGUGCCAGUGCUGUCCUCAGUAUUGCUGCUGCUAUAUCCGCUGUCCCUGCUGUCCUGCCCACUGCUGCUGUCCUGAGGAAGCCCUGGCCCGCCACCGCUACAUGAAGCAGGCCCAGGCCCUAGGUCCUCAGAUGAUGGGAAAACCCCUGUACUGGGGGGCGGACAGGAGCUCCCAGGUUUCAUCUUAUCCAAUGCACCCGCUGCUGCAGCGAGAUUUGUCCCUGCCGUCCAGCCUCCCGCAGAUGCCAAUGACCCAGACCACCAAUCAGCCUCCCAUCGCCAAUGGUGUCCUGGAGUAUUUGGAGAAAGAACUGCGGAACCUCAACCUGGCCCAGCCUCUGCCCCCUGACCUCAAAGGCAGAUUUGGCCAUCCCUGCAGCAUGCUGUCCUCCCUGGGCUCUGAGGUCGUGGAACGCAGAAUCAUCCACCUGCCCCCACUGAUCAGAGACCUGUCAUCCUCAAGGAGGACCAGUGACUCCCUGCACCAGCAGUGGCUCACCCCAAUUCCCUCCAGGCCCUGGGAUCUGAGGGAGGGGAGAAGCCACCACCAUUACCCUGAUUUCCACCAGGAGCUCCAGGACCGGGGGCCAAAGUCUUGGGCAUUGGAAAGAAGGGAGUUGGACCCAUCGUGGAGUGGAAGGCACCGUAGCUCUAGGCUGAAUGGGUCACCCAUACACUGGUCAGACAGGGACAGCCUAAGCGAUGUCCCCUCAUCCAGUGAGGCACGCUGGCGGCCGAGCCACCCUCCUUUCAGGAGCCGCUGUCAGGAGAGGCCCCGCAGGCCCAGCCCCCGGGAGAGCACUCAGAGGCACGGGAGACGACGCAGGCACCGCAGCUACUCUCCUCCCUUGCCCUCCGGCCUCAGUUCCUGGAGCUCUGAAGAGGACAAGGAGAGGCAGCCCCAGAGCUGGCGGGCCCACCGCCGCGGCUCGCACUCCCCACACUGGCCCGAGGAGAAGCCGCCUAGCUACCGCUCACUUGAUAUCACUCCAGGCAAGAAUAGCAGGAAAAAAGGGAGUGUGGAGAGGCGCUCGGAGAAAGACAGCUCUCAUAGUGGAAGGAGUGUGGUCAUUUAGUCACCAAGCACAGCACAACUUCUGUGGCUACUUCUCGGCUCCUGUGUGUCAUCAGCAUCACCUAGGUUUCCAGCUGACUUGGGAACUGCAAGUCUGAGUCUAACAGUUUUUGGCUUAGAUUCUGAGAAUCAAAUAGAAGAAUUUUAAAUACAAGAGUUUGAGAUUGGGUAUAGUGGCUCACACCUGUAAUCACAGCACUUUGGGAGGCUAAGAAUCACUUGAGACUAGGAGUUCAAGAUCAGCCUGGGAAACAUAGUGAGACCCCGUCUCUACAAAAAAUAUAAAAAUUAGUUAGGUGUGGUGGCAUGCACUUGUAGUCCCAGCUACUCAAGAGGCUGAGGCAGAAGGAUCCCUUGAGCCCAGGAGUGCAAGGCUGCAAUGAGCCAGGAUCCCAUGAUCACACAUCUGUAUUCCAGCCUGGGCAAUAGAGCAAGUCCCCAUUACUAAAAAACCCAAAAGGCCAAAAAACAAAAAAGUUAGAGUUCGAGGAAUUACCAACUGUAGUUUUAGCCUUGGUUCAUGCUCUCUUGCAUAUUUAUAUAAUCUCUGACUUGUAAUGGACCCUGACUGGAAUGUGAUCCCUCAGGAACUUAGUAGCCUGAGUCUUUCAGUAGACUACACUGCCCAGAACCCUGGCCAUUCUCAAAAUGAGAACUUGGGAAUGUUUAAGAAGAAAUCAAACAUGUUUCAGGAAAAGGAAAUCUAUGGAGUAUUAUAGGGACAUUCCCAUGGGAAUGUAUCUUCCUCCAUGGCAUGUCUUGAGGGUCCUUUCUUGUUAGGAGUUUAUCCUGCCAGCCCAUAAAUGGACUAUUUAUUGUAAGUGUAGAAAAUCACAGAGAAGCAGUUUUGCACCAGCCUUAUUCCUGUGCCUUGUUUUCCUCUUGCUCUUUUUUUACCUGUAUAUCUAAUUUAUAUUUUCAUAUAUAUUGUGUAUUGAUUGAAGUCACUUUAAAUCCUUCUUGGGAAUGACACAGUAUAUAAAUAAGGAAGAAAGAAAACAUGCCAAGCUGAGCAUGCUGCUCCAAAUAAAUAUCUGCUUUCCUA